AACGCUUUGCGUCCCGACGCCCGCAGGUCCUCGCGGUGCGCACCGUUUGCGACUUGGUACUUGGAAAAAUGGACAAGGAUUGUGAAAUGAAACGCACCACACUGGACAGCCCUUUGGGGAAGCUGGAGCUGUCUGGUUGUGAGCAGGGUCUGCACGAAAUAAAGCUCCUGGGCAAGGGGACGUCUGCAGCUGAUGCCGUGGAGGUCCCAGCCCCCGCUGCGGUUCUCGGAGGUCCGGAGCCCCUGAUGCAGUGCACAGCCUGGCUGAAUGCCUAUUUCCACCAGCCCGAGGCUAUCGAAGAGUUCCCCGUGCCGGCUCUUCACCAUCCCGUUUUCCAGCAAGAGUCGUUCACCAGACAGGUGUUAUGGAAGCUGCUGAAGGUUGUGAAAUUCGGAGAAGUGAUUUCUUACCAGCAAUUAGCAGCCCUGGCAGGCAACCCCAAAGCCGCGCGAGCAGUGGGAGGAGCAAUGAGAGGCAAUCCUGUCCCCAUCCUCAUCCCGUGCCACAGAGUGGUCUGCAGCAGCGGAGCCGUGGGCAACUACUCCGGAGGACUGGCCGUGAAGGAAUGGCUUCUGGCCCAUGAAGGCCACCGGUUGGGGAAGCCAGGCUUGGGAGGGAGCUCAGGUCUGGCAGGGGCCUGGCUCAAGGGAGCGGGAGCUACCUCGGGCUCCCCGCCUGCUGGCCGAAACUGAGUAUGUGCAGUAGGAUGGAUGUUUGAGCGACACACACGUGUAACACUGCAUCGGAUGCGGGGCGUGGAGGCACCGCUGUAUUAAAGGAAGUGGCAGUGUCCUGGGAACAAGCGUGUCUGCCCUUUCUGUUUCCAUAUUUUACAGCAGGAUGAGUUCAGACGCCCGCGGUCCUGCACACAUUUGUUUCCUUCUCUAACGCUGCCCUUGCUCUAUUUUUCAUGUCCAUUAAAACAGGCCAAGUGAGUGUGGAAGGCCUGGCUCAUGUUGGGCCACAGCCCAGGAUGGGGCAGUCUGGCACCCUCAGGCCACAGACGGCUGCCAUAGCCGCUGUCCAGGGCCAGCUAAGGCCCAUCCCAGGCCGUCCACACUAGAAAGCUGGCCCUGCCCCAUCCCCACCAUGCCUCCCUUCCUGGCUGUGUCCAUGGCUGUGAUGGCAUUCUCCACUCAGCAGUUCCUAGCAUCCCACACCCAGGUCUCACUGAAAGAAAGGGGAACAGGCCAUGGCAGUCAGUGCUUACAGAGGUUUUCUAGCUUUGUUUCCUACCUGCCAAAAAGGCUAAUGCAAGAUGCAUCCACUUAUGGUCUGUAUCAGGUGAAUAGAAAAUAACCAUUUGCCAAGAUUUGGAAAGACAGAGAGCUCUCUGGACACGGGUUCGAUGGAGCUUGCACCUCUCUGAGAGCUGAAGUCAAGUCUCACCCUCUCUCCAUACUCCCUGGCCUAGUGUGCUCUGGGCAGCAGGUAGGAAGGGACAGGGACCUCUCAUCUCAAGGGCUGCCCCAAAGGGCCCUCAGGGACCAUGGGCCUGUUAGGACCCCAGCACCCCAGUGUCGAUCCUGGAAGUCAAAGGUCACGACUGUGGGGGGCCAGCUCAUGUCACUGAUGGCAGCAGGCAGGGUUUCCAGCAUGGGCGGUGCGCUGCUGUCUGAUACUUCAUUAUUGUGUUGUCAUCCUAGCUGUAUAAUUAACUAUAUCCAAAAGCCGGAAGGGAAACCUGUAGCUCUGCAUAUGGAGAAAUAAAACAGAGCAUAUGAUGUAUAGAGAAAAUGAACUGCACCCAGCUGUGCACUAGAGCGCCAUGUUCUUACCCAGCAUUCCUUGCCACGGUGUGAACCACAGCAGGGAAGCUCGCAUGGUUCUACACGUCACCGAGGCCUGGAUGAAAAUGUGGCCUCACGAUGUGUAUGGUUGGGACCCGCCUUCUAUUUCAUUUUAUCUUAACACCAACGAAAGAAAACCGAUUUCAGACGUUUUUCGCUGAUUUAUGAUUUAUUAUAUCCCUUUCUGGCAUCAGCCAAAAUCUCGGUUUUUCCUAUGACAUGAAGUGAUGUGACUCUUACCCCGUUGUCUUAACUCUUGGUAUUUUUGAAGCAGGAUAAGUCACACAGCGGGUCACGUAGACACGUGCUGUUUUGUGGGACAGGCCCUGGGCCUCCUUGCUCCUGGCAGGCCUCAGGUGCCGCACGCCGCGUCACCGUCAGGACUCGCAGGCUGUCUGGUCAUUUUUGACGUUGCUGAAGGUGAGUGGGAAAAGCUGGGUGCACUCUGCCCCAAAGGUGGUGCCCUGUGUCCCCCACAGAUGAUGGCCCUCCCCAGUGAUGGCCGGUCACCAGGCACGGCUUUCCCCUCUGCAUGAACAGAACAGAAGCUUCUGGCUCUCCAAGGCAGCAGCUUGGGGCCUGGUGGCCCGGGUGUGCGAGCCGCGAGUGCUUUCCAACAGAGGGCACCAGAGCCGUGCGGUGUGCUGUGGAGACCCCAGCACCACUUCCCCUGCUGGAGGAUGGAUUUGAAGGAGGGUGGCUGGGCGGCACCCCGAUGGCUCCCUGUGCUCCCUGAGACCCUACAGGCCGCCCUCUGCAGCCACACCUGGACCGGCAGGCAUGCACGCUGCAGGCAGGCUGCCUCCGCUGUUUGGGUCCCAUGAACGAUGGAAGCCUCCCAGUGAGAUCUUCAGGUCUCUCAUCAGGCACAGGCUCUGAGGGAGGGUCCUGGGGCCACAUGACUGCAGCCAGCGAGGGCCGAGCCCCCAGAAUCCAGGUCAGCUCCUGGUGGCAGGGGACCUGCCCGUCAAAGCCGUCCAAGGUGAGCCAGCAAAUCCGUGUGGCCUGGGAGCACAGGUGGGCCUGCUCGGACCAUGCCCUUGGUGCAGUACAAAACCAUGUUCUGCUUCCUCUCCGAGGGUUUCCGCGGCCCUGUCAGAACAGGCUUGAUAGAUGCCCGGAGGUUCCCUCUGACAGCCGCAGCAGCAGGGCUCAAACCGGCGGGGCCGUGUACCGCUCCAAGGACAAGCUCUGCCGAGGCCGACAUGAAAAGCCAGCACGCGGGUCGCCUAGAGCCGCUCUGCCUCCAAGCUGCAGCGCCGUUCGUGAAAAUACAGAGGGAGAGGGAAGGCACAAAGAAAUACAAAACUAUUUUCCAAAUAAAAAGAAAUGUCGAAACAAGAAAGCUGUGUUCUUCAGCCUUGGCCCUGGGUCCCCCUCACCCUGUCGCAUUUCCCAGCACUGUGAUGCUUUGAAGGCCGACACCGAGACCCGCCGUGCACGACAGCCACCUCGCAGCCACUCAGACCGGCGGACCACGCUCCCCUGUUUCCAGAGAGAUGAGAGAGUCAGAAGUAAUACUUGUUUUUGCAGAACCACACUUGUGGCAAAAUAAGUUGCCUUUGGCCACGCAGGAGACUGAGUUUUGUGAGGGGUUGUCCUUCUCCCAGUCUCUCUUCCCGCUGGGAACAGAAGUGUCCAGUAAACCCACCUGCAUUCCACGUGUCCUGUGGCCGCCUCCAGUGGUGAGUCUGUGAGGCCAGAGAAGAGAAGCUAUGACCGUGCAAACAUGCAUGUUAUGGUGUUGGCUGAUGCGGAAUCAGGAAGCUUGGAGGAGCUCUUGCAUGAGGAAUUGCAGAACUUAGGGGCAUGAAUUUGCACUUCCAGAUGUGAAGGUUGCAGGCACCGGGCGUUGCAGAGGAAGUGGGCAAGCUCACCUUGUAGAGAACUUACUUGGGGUUUGUAAUUUGUAUACACUUCUUACCCAGCAGAAACAGCUUACUGAACACCCCUCGGGUGGCUGGAUGAUGUGCUAGCAACUGAAACCAUCUCUGCGACUUAAGCUUCUCUGGUGCGUCGCGCCCCACGUGCUUCUCCAGAAUCCCGUUUGGAGGGGCCAAGCAAGUCCAAUAUAGAUAGGUUUAUACUGAAGCCAUCAGUUUUGUUUCUUACAUCGUUUGUAAACAGCAGUAUUAUCCUGGAACUUGUUUCCUACAGAACUGUAAGAUAAGGAUAAAAUCCCAUCCACCUGAAUUGCUGAGAAACGUAAGAGGUGGUGUGACCCGCUGGAGCCCUGUGGAGUGGCGGACUCUGGGGAGUAGCUGGUCAGUGAGAUUCUCGCAGCAAUGUGAGGCAUCCUCCUCACAGAAAUGCAUUUACGGAUGUUGCUGUAUCCCCUGACCUGGCCUACAAGGACAGAACAGCCCUGGGGGCCACGUCCCCUCCCGGUCUCAUCUGCCGCUUGCUCACCUUGGCUGUCCAUGCACCCGUAGCUGUGACCAUGGGCGGUGGCGCCAGCUCGGACUUCACCCCGUUGGAGCGGGCAGGAUGUCACACUGAGCUAAUGUGAGAUUGUUCAUGAAGCUACAGAUCUUAGUGCUACUUGGGCUUCUCACAGCACAGAGGAGGAUUCUGAAGUGAGAGAUAAAUUGGCUUCAUGUAUGAGCAAGGGGGAAAGUGUUUUAUUUUACUAGGAAGAUUUUACUGAAAGACCAAUCCCGAAACGGCCCUUGCUUCGGCCACAGCUGCUGGGAUGUCCUCGGGCCUCCCCUGUUUGUCUGCAUGUCUUCUUGUUGCCAUCGGGGCAGUGGAGUCCCCGGAAACAGUCCAAGGCCCUGGGGUGGGGGAUUUAAAUUUUUGGCUUCCCUCAGACCUCAGACCGUGUGGGUUUUUUUUUCUUUCUUUCUUUCCUGUUCAUGGGCAUUUGAUUAAAAGUUUGUGUUUAAAGA